CCCUUGCUUUUGGUGAUGGUUGUGAGUGCAGAAGUUGAUUGACAGAUGCAUGCCAGAAACCCCCAUUCUCCUUUUCAAAGACAACAUAUGAUGGAUUGCUAUCUCUCAGCGCAGCAGGACACGGGGACCAUGCAAGCUGUAAUUGGUCAGGCAUGAACUCUCUUGGGUUGUGUUACCCUGUUUGCUGUUUACUGUCAAGAUGCUGAAAGAAUGUUCUUAUAAUGAUCCAAGAGGAAGUGGCAAAUGAGUGCUCUUCUUCAGGAUCCAAUGAUAGCUGGACAAGUCAGUAAGCCCUUGCUGUCAGUGCGGAGUGAAAUGAAUGCGGAGUUGAGAGGUGAGGACAAGGCUGCUACUUCAGACAGCGAGCUGAAUGAGCCCCUGCUUGCGCCUGUGGAAUCAAAUGACAGCGAGGACACUCCCAGCAAGCUCUUCGGGGCUAGAGGAAACCCAGCAUUAUCAGACCCAGGCACUCCUGACCAACACCAGGCCAGUCAGACCCACCCCCCAUUUCCAGUUGGGCCACAGCCACUUCUGACGGCACAGCAGUUAGCUUCUGCUGUGGCCGGCGUGAUGCCGGGAGGCCCCCCAGCCCUCAACCAGCCAAUCCUCAUUCCCUUCAACAUGGCGGGACAGCUAGGAGGCCAGCAAGGACUGGUUCUCACACUGCCAACAGCGAAUCUCACCAACAUCCAAGGGCUGGUGGCAGCAGCUGCAGCCGGAGGCAUUAUGACUCUGCCACUGCAAAAUCUACAAGCUACCUCAUCCCUGAACUCCCAGCUCCAGCAGCUCCAGCUCCAGCUCCAGCAGCAGCAGCAGCAGCAGCAGCAGCAGCCUCCCCCGUCAACCAACCAGCACCCGCAACCAGCCCCACAGGCGCCCUCGCAGUCCCAGCAGCAGCCGCUGCAGCCCACCCCACCCCAGCAGCCACCACCCGCCUCUCAGCAGCCGCCAGCUCCUACAUCUCAGCUGCAACAGGCGCCUCAGCCCCAGCAGCACCAACCCCACUCCCACUCCCAGAACCAGAACCAACCAUCUCCAACCCAGCAGAGCUCCAGCCCCCCGCAGAAACCUAGUCAGUCUCCAGGACAUGGCCUGCCUUCACCGCUCACGCCACCCAAUCCUCUACAGCUGGUUAAUAAUCCACUAGCAAGUCAGGCUGCAGCGGCUGCAGCAGCCAUGAGCUCCAUAGCAAGCUCACAGGCCUUUGGCAAUGCCCUCUCCAGUCUUCAGGGGGUCACAGGUCAACUAGUUACUAAUGCACAAGGACAGAUUAUCGGGACCAUUCCACUGAUGCCUAAUCCAGGGCCAUCGAGCCAAGCAGCAAGCGGCACUCAGGGCUUGCAAGUGCAGCCAAUCACCCCCCAGCUCCUCACAAACGCCCAGGGCCAGAUCAUCGCCACAGUCAUUGGGAACCAGAUCCUGCCCGUGAUCAACACCCAGGGCAUCACGCUGUCACCCAUCAAGCCCGGCCAGCAGCUCCACCAACCCUCCCAGACGUCAGUGGGUCAAGCAGCCUCCCAAGGCAACCUUCUGCACCUGGCUCACAGCCAAGCAUCCAUGUCUCAAAGUCCCGUCCGGCAGGCUUCCUCUUCUUCCUCCUCAUCCUCCUCUUCUUCAGCUUUGAGCGUGGGCCAGUUAGUCAGCAAUCCUCAAACGGCAGCGGGUGAGGUGGAUGGGGUUAAUCUGGAGGAGAUCCGAGAAUUUGCCAAAGCUUUUAAAAUCCGGCGCCUGUCCCUUGGCCUGACCCAGACUCAGGUGGGACAGGCUCUCAGUGCUACAGAGGGCCCCGCGUACAGCCAGUCGGCCAUCUGCAGACACACCAUCCUGAGAAGCCACUUUUUCCUACCACAGGAAGCCCAAGAGAACACUAUAGCUAGCAGUCUGACAGCCAAACUGAACCCUGGCCUUUUGUAUCCUGCCAGGUUUGAAAAGCUGGACAUCACCCCUAAAAGUGCCCAGAAGAUCAAGCCGGUGCUUGAGCGGUGGAUGGCUGAGGCUGAGGCCCGCCAUCGAGCAGGUAUGCAGAACCUGACCGAGUUUAUCGGGAGUGAACCAUCCAAAAAGCGCAAGCGGCGCACCUCCUUCACACCCCAGGCCCUUGAGAUCCUCAAUGCCCACUUUGAGAAGAACACACACCCUUCUGGGCAGGAAAUGACCGAAAUUGCUGAGAAGCUGAACUAUGACCGAGAAGUAGUUAGAGUUUGGUUCUGCAAUAAGAGGCAAGCCCUGAAGAACACAAUUAAACGCUUAAAACAGCACGAGCCGGCCACGGCAGUCCCUUUGGAGCCCUUAACAGACUCUCUGGAAGAAAACUCCUAAAGAGAUGCCCACCCAUAAUCAGAAGCAAAAUUCACAGAAACUAAACUCCACCCUUGGGACUCCACAACAACAACAACAACAAAAUUUAAUUUAAUUUAAAAAUAGCCCCAGUCGUCAUCACCCUUGUAAGUAAAUGACUAAGAAAACUACCAAGUGGACAGAAUGGUUUCUACAUGUCCGUUGGUUUUCCAAAAAGGAAAGAAGAAAAUUUUUAGAAAAUUUUUAAACAAGGAAUACACCACACUGAAGGUGUGUGUGGUAGGAUAGUUCCCUUCCCCCACCUGUCUCCCCCAAAGCCAGUUUUUUAAUGGACUUAAAGCAAACCAAAUAACCACGUACUUUUUUCUGUAUAUUAUGAAAAUGUGAACACAUUUUAAGGAAAAAGAAAAAAAAAAACUAAACCAAAAACCAACAACGAAGGAACAAAAACUUUGAUCUGUUCAAAGCGAAUACAAGCCUGCCACCUGGAGGAAGGACUGCACCCCUUCAGGUACUAAGUGCUGAUUCACUAUGAAACCUAUUAACCAAAGUCAGAAACAUGGCAUUGCAACGCGAUCGUUCGUCUACGCUUCUCCGCACGUAAAGUUGUGUUACGAAUUUUUACAUUUGUACUAACAGAACAAUAGGAAGCCUGAUUUCUCCCAUCUUUCCCAUCUACUGUCUCCACCCAUGGGGUGGGUACCAUUGUUGAAGCCAUUCUGUGAGGCUCACUAUUGGGUUUUUUUGUGGGGGUGGUAGGGAGGGUGGUCUUUUUUCUUUGUCUUUCUUUUUGACGGGAGGGCAUCCUGGAUCGUGUGCCAAAGCAUUUGUUGCUUUUUUCUCACUAUGACUUGUGGGUUUGAGAAAAGAAAAUGGAGCUCGCAUUUCUCUCUUUUCCUCCAUUUCUCCAUCUCCCUCGCGCGUGGCUCCUGGGGUCUGCUGGAAGGCCACAGAAGUGGGGAGAAGCAGUGUCUUUUCCACUCAGAUCCUAGUGAAAUGCAGGAGAGACUCCAAAAUAACUAGGGCUUUGCUCGAUGAACUGUCAACACUGGCAUAAGCUGUAAUUGUGCUCACUGUCCACACCAGAGCUUGGGAUUUUUCUCAGUCUGUUGGCCACGUACAUGGAGAGCUGACCAAAACUAAUUUUGUAAUAUAAACAUAAGCUGCACAUUUGGUUCAAUACUUACAUCUAUGUUAUGCUUCUGUGCAAAGCAAUUUCUCUCAGAAGUCUGAUAGCCAAAGAAAUGUCUCAAGAUUUCAGUCAAAUACACACAUGACAUGCACACACCCAUAAACACACACACAAAGAAACAGGCUAAAAAGAAAGUGAUAGCAACUGGAUCAUUAAAGGCCAUCGUGUAUCCUGUUAAUCUCAUCUUUUCUGCUACUUCUUUCAUUCCAAUAGCGAUGGCAGACUUUUUUCAGGGGGAAUAAUUACUCUUCGGGAUAUAUAAAUGGAGCAGAAAGGUGGCGGGCAAAUUUAAACAACUGGAAUUGGGGGCCAGGUUCUUCAGGGGAAAGGAAGUUUGAAGAAGCUUUCACCAAAAGAAAAAAAUAUAGAAGGGGCUUAUCUAACAAUCAGAAUAGCCUGCAAUAUGAGAACUAGAGGAUUAUUUCCUUUAAAAAAAAUAACUUAAAAGAUCUGUGGGCCACAAUAACCUAAUAAGCAAGGACAUGUUGGGAUGUGAGGACGGCUGUGCAGGUGAGCACUUGGCAGCUGCCACUGGUGUUUUCACCCAGGUACAGGCAGACGGUGUUCCAUUAAAGGAGCAGGCAAAAGAGAGCUGUCAAUUUGCUUGCUGUUGAAAUGUACAUAUUUAUGCAUAAUUUAUAAUCAUGCUAAUGUAUUAUCUAGAAGUAAGUUGUGAAAGAAAAAAGAGAAACCCAAUCUCAAGUUGCCCAACUGAUUAGAAAUGCCAUCUCCUUCCCCUAAUACACUCCCUCUCCCUGGGGAGUUUGAGUUUCUUCUGUUGGCUCCUUUGCUGUUUGUGUAAAUGCUACAGUAUAAUUGUCCCCUCCAAUGAUUCAUGCAGCAAUCAAGAGACUACCAGCAAGGAAACUCUAAAAGGAAUCCUGGAAGUGGAACAAGUCACUCGUAAAGGUGUUUCCAUUUUACCAGUCAAUGCUAACUGGACCACAGCUAACUUGAUCUUCAAUGCCAACAUCACAGAGCCCCUUUCGCCACCUCAAAAACUGCACAAACAUGGACAACCCAGAAACCCAAAACUUUAUUGAUUAAAACAGAUUUUGGAUUCUCCUAGGACCUGCUCCAAAUUCCAUCAAGAAAAGCUCCCUGCGAAGAGAAGUUAACAAGAUAACAUAUGAUGGAUGCUAAAUAUUUAAAUAUAUGCCGGCAGCGGUUACAUAAGGCCUGCUCAGUUCUGAGAUCUAUAAUUGGGAGGGUCUAACUAGGACAGGGAAAAUAUAAAAUAAAAGUAAUCUUCCAGAGUGGAACAAAAAAGAAAUAUAUUCAUCCGACAGUCGUAACACCAUUCAUGUGCAGUGAUUUUUUUAUAGUUUUAUAAUUUUGUAUUGUUUUAUAAAUUAUUUAUAAGGUGUUGUAAUGCUUCUUAUAUUAAUUUUUUACAGAUAAAUUUUUUGCUACAAGGCAUAAAAAGGUGCCUGAACCGAUUCUUAGGAAUAUAAAUUAUACUGUGUAACUCAUAAGUCUUUGGGACCACACCUAAUGCUUAAUUUUAUGAUGACAUUUCUCAUGUCUACUUGUAAACAACUUCAUAUGCCAAUGGCGUUUAAGUGUCUUUUAUGUUUCCAUGAACUGAAGGUUAAGGUUGCCACCCACAAAAAAUAAAAGCCACUUUGGGCAUAUGUGAUUGUAUUUCAAGCUUCAGUAUUUUUCUCACAUAAUUUUUAAUUAUUGUUAUCUGCAUUUUCAUUACUUCAUGAAAAAAUGACAGUGGAUAUUACAUUUUACACUUGUUUAUAGAUUUUCUUUCUUUUUCAACCAAGAAAAUAUUUUGAACAAUUGAAACUUUUAAUUGCAUUUGCAAGGUUUUGGCUUCUUUAUGUUGUCAUCACACAGAUGCACACACACAUACACAUACAACACAAAAGAGAGAACAAAAAAGCAAAAGGAGCUAGGAAAAAAACAAAACAAAACAAGUAGAGGUGUAUCAAAGAACUCAAGCUAUAACCAAAAAGAAAUCGUAAAAUGCCUUUGCUCGUUUCUCUACGCUGGACCAAAGCUCAAUAUUUGUAGGUAUAUGCACAUUGUAUAGAUAUGGCUAAAUGUUGCUGACAAUCUCGCAAUACUAAACUGUUCCUAUUUUAAGAAAAAAAAAAGAAAUACAAACUGUUCAUCAAUGUUUUACCUCAGCACUCUACUUGUACCCAGUUAAUGACCAAGCUUAAAAAAAAAUUGAGAUAAAGGAAAUUGAUUUUCAUUUCAAUGUUUGACUGUAAAAUCUGUUUGGAUAACAUUUUGUAAUGAGCUUUUUGUCAUGUGAUUUGCUUGUCUUCAACUUGAAAUUAUGUGAGGCACAUUUGUUUAUUUGUUGUUAAGAAAGUGAUUUUUUUUUUUUUUUGUCCUAUGUGCUGUGAUCUAGACUGGUCACCGGGGUCACUUAUGAGGCACCACAAAGAGAUCUGCUUCUCCGUGCCCGGAGCAGGCAGCAGGAGGGAGGGCAGGAAACAGGACUGGGUUGCUUUGGAAAAAUCAUCAUGACAAGAAGUUGACAUGAUAGACUUGUGACCAAGAAGCCAAACUGAAUAUUUAAAAGCUCCUUACUUGCUCUGACAUUGAAACCAAAGCUGAUUUUAUCUGCACAGGUUGCUUAAUAUUUAAAAAAAAAAAAAACUGUACUUAAUCUAGAGCAAUAUCUGUAUGGUCAGUAAAGCUGCACUUUGUGUAUUUCUUAACAGCUUCAGAUCUGUCACUUUUAAUUUGUACCAUAAAAAAUAAAUAAUUGUUUGACAUGA